AUUCUGCAAGCCACCCUGGGGUGCAGCUGAGCUAGACAUGGGACGGCGAGACGCCCAGCUCCUGGCAGCGCUCCUCGUCCUGGGGCUAUGUGCCCUGGCGGGGAGUGAGAAACCCUCCCCCUGCCAGUGCUCCAGGCUGAGCCCCCAUAACAGGACGAACUGCGGCUUCCCUGGAAUCACCAGUGACCAGUGUUUUGACAAUGGAUGCUGUUUCGACUCCAGUGUCACUGGGGUCCCCUGGUGUUUCCACCCCCUCCCAAAGCAAGAGUCGGAUCAGUGCGUCAUGGAGGUCUCAGACCGAAGAAACUGUGGCUACCCGGGCAUCAGCCCCGAGGAAUGCGCCUCUCGGAAGUGCUGCUUCUCCAACUUCAUCUUUGAAGUGCCCUGGUGCUUCUUCCCGAAGUCUGUGGAAGACUGCCAUUACUAAGAGAGGCUGGUUCCAGAGGAUGCAUCUGGCUCACCGGGUGUUCCGAAACCAAAGAAGAAACUUCGCCUUAUCAGCUUCAUACUUCAUGAAAUCCUGGGUUUUCUUAACCAUCUUUUCCUCAUUUUCAAUGGUUUAACAUAUAAUUUCUUUAAAUAAAACCCUUAAAAUCUGCUAAA